AGUUGGCCGUCAGCUGCGCCAGAGGCAGGUGCCAGCGGAGAGUGGGUGGGGGUGCCGGCGCCAGGCCAGGCUCGGGGAGGCCCCGCGCUACCUCUGCCUCUAGGAGUCCAGGCGCACAGACAAGCUCCCCGGAGCCGCUCCUGCUUCGCCAACUCCCCACUCGCGCCGCCCGUGCCAGCCGCCGGCACUGGCGUCUCCGCCGCCCGCAGGAGGAGUCGCGGGAGCACUAGCAGCCGCCGCCGAGCGACAGCAUCCUCAGGAGAGACGCCCCGGGCUUUGCAGCCGGCGGCCUCCGUCCGCCCUCCGCGGUCGCCCCCCGCCCCGUCGCCCGUCCGCCCGCGGUGGCAGCCGGCGCCGGCGCCCCGGGGCCCUUCACCUGCCGCGAGCGUCCGGGCGGGCGGGCGCACGGGAGAAAAGGCGCAAGAAGCGGGCACCCCGGGAACCCCAUUCCCUCGGCUCACUCGGCGCGGAGAAGCGACGCCCGCUGACUCCGAGAGCCCCGGUGCUCCGUGCACCUGGUCCCCAAGUUGAGGAGCGACACCCCUCCACAGGGGACUAGCCCGCGCGGGGAGCAUUCCGGUCUCACUGACCCCGGCCCACCCGCGGGACUCCAGGCACCUCUUCUGCCCGCACCCCGCGACCCCUCCCGGGACCCCGGAGACAGCCGGCCUGCCCCCGGCGUCCCCCUUGGCCAGCACGCCAUGCCGGGGCUGCGCCGGGACCGCCUACUGACUCUGCUGCUGCUGGGCGCGCUGCUCUCCGCCGACCUCUACUUCCACCUCUGGCCCCAAGUACAGCGCCAGCUGCGGCCUCGGGAGCGCCCGCGGGGGUGCCCGUGCACCGGCCGCGCCUCCUCCCUGGCGCGGGACUCGGCCGCAGCUGCCUCGGACCCCGGCACGAUCGUGCACAACUUUUCCCGAACCGAGCCCCGGACUGAACCGGCUGGCGGCAGCCACAGCGGGUCGAGCUCCAAGUUGCAGGCCCUCUUCGCCCACCCGCUGUACAACGUCCCGGAGGAGCCGCCUCUCCUGGGAGCCGAGGACUCGCUCCUGGCCAGCCAGGAGGCGCUGCGGUAUUACCGGAGGAAGGUGGCCCGCUGGAACAGGCCUCAGUUCCUGCUUUUGAAAGGAAGAGGGGGAGUCUGUGACCCCUGAGGCCUCCUUGCAACUCUGUUUUCCAAGCUUUGCACAUCUUCCGAAUUUCUUCUUCAAAGUCUACCCUAAUGAAAUAUCAGACAAUUUUCCAAGUGUGCUUCAUGAACUUCUGGGAGGUGCUUCACAGUUUCUGCAAAUGAUUGAUUGAAUUUUCACUUUGAAAAAAUAUACUUUAAGGCGACACAAGAUGUACAGAGAGCAGAUGAACCUUACCUCCCUGGACCCCCCACUGCAGCUCCGACUCGAGGCCAGCUGGGUCCAGUUCCACCUGGGUAUUAACCGCCAUGGGCUCUACUCCCGGUCCAGCCCUGUUGUCAGCAAACUUCUGCAAGACAUGAGGCACUUUCCCACCAUCAGUGCUGAUUACAGUCAAGAUGAGAAAGCCUUGCUGGGGGCAUGUGACUGCACCCAGAUUGUGAAACCCAGUGGGGUCCACCUCAAGCUGGUGCUGAGGUUCUCGGAUUUCGGGAAGGCCAUGUUCAAACCCAUGAGACAGCAGCGAGAUGAGGAGACACCAGUGGACUUCUUCUACUUCAUUGACUUUCAGAGACACAAUGCUGAGAUCGCAGCUUUCCAUCUGGACAGGAUUCUGGACUUCCGACGGGUGCCGCCAACAGUGGGGAGGAUAGUAAAUGUCACCAAGGAAAUCCUAGAGGUCACCAAGAAUGAAAUCCUGCAGAGUGUUUUCUUUGUCUCUCCAGCGAGCAACGUGUGCUUCUUCGCCAAGUGUCCAUACAUGUGCAAGACGGAGUAUGCUGUCUGUGGCAACCCACACCUGCUGGAGGGUUCCCUCUCUGCCUUCCUGCCGUCCCUCAACCUGGCCCCCAGGCUGUCUGUGCCCAACCCCUGGAUCCGCUCCUACACACUGGCAGGAAAAGAGGAGUGGGAGGUCAAUCCCCUUUACUGUGACACAGUGAAACAGAUCUACCCGUACAACAACAGCCAGCGGCUCCUCAAUGUCAUCGACAUGGCCAUCUUCGACUUCUUGAUAGGGAAUAUGGACCGGCACCAUUAUGAGAUGUUCACCAAGUUCGGGGAUGAUGGGUUCCUUAUUCACCUUGACAACGCCAGAGGGUUCGGACGACACUCCCAUGAUGAAAUCUCCAUCCUCUCGCCUCUCUCCCAGUGCUGCAUGAUAAAAAAGAAAACACUUUUGCACCUGCAGCUGCUGGCCCAAGCUGACUACAGACUCAGCGAUGUGAUGCGAGAAUCACUGCUGGAAGACCAGCUCAGCCCUGUCCUCACUGAACCCCACCUCCUUGCCCUGGAUCGAAGGCUCCAAACCAUCCUAAGGACAGUGGAGGGGUGCAUAGUGGCCCAUGGACAGCAGAGUGUCAUAGUCGACGGCCCAGUGGAACAGUUGGCCCCAGACUCUGGCCAGGCUAACUUGACAAGCUAAGGGCUGGCAGAGUCCAGUUUCAGAAAAUACGCCUGGAGCCAGAGCAGUCGACUCGAGUGCCGACCCUGCGUCCUCACUCCCACCUGUUACUGCUGGGAGUCAAGUCAGCUAGGAAGGAAGCAGGACAUUUUCUCAAACAGCAAGUGGGGCCCAUGGAACUGAAUCUUUACUCCUUGGUGCACCGCUUCUGUCGUGCGUUGCCUUGCUCCGUUUUUCCCAAAAAGCACUGGCUUCAUCAAGGCCACCGACGAUCUCCUGAGUGCACUGGGAAAUCUGGGUAUAGGUCAGGCUUGGCAGCCUUGAUCCCAGGAGAGUACUAAUGGUAACAAGUCAAAUAAAAGGACAUCAAGUGGAUACCUGACUUCUCAGGAUCCUUAUUCUAGCUACAAGUCAAAGAUAACUCCUGGUCCAGACAAAACACCUGGCCUAUCACAAGCUGACUAAAAAUCUGCACUUUGGGCCAGCGCAGGCAACAGUAACUCUGACAGGUUCAAAUUAGACCUCACACUUUCUACUCAUAUUCUAGUCACUGGACCCAUCUGAAUCAGUAAUCCCUACUGCCCGGUCCUGGAGUAACUUCUUAGAGAUAUUAUAACAAGUGGCAAAAAUAAAAGAGGGAUUUGCUAAGAAUAUCAGAAAAGGAGUGUUCCAAUUUGAAGAGUAUUACAAUUGAAAUAACAUCAAAUAUGUCACACUAAGCAGCCAGUAACAGAAUAAAUAAUUACAACGAAGGAAAAAAAAAGGAAAGUCCUCCAAGGUCAGGAUGGCAUGGGAACAGGCCUAGCAGGGACACAAGCCUGGAGUAAGGCAGGAAAAGAGCCAAGGCUGACUACAGCCCACCAACCACAAUCUUCUUCCCUAAGACCCCAGGAUUGUCCCCGGCCCAUCCCCAAAAGAAGAAAGGGGCUAUGUGGAAAGGUGAGGCCCUCUAGAUGCCCCUCCCUGUGACGGCUGGCUCAAAAAAGACUAAGUCAGGUUUUUUAUUGAAGCCUCCCUUAGAAGAAAGUGUAGUAGGGAUUCCUUGUCUCCUCUACCUUCUCCCUGACUUGUUGAUAUCUGAAACUCCUUUUAAUAGGAGGCUUUGUUUCUUAUUCCAUAAUUAAUGACCGAAAACACAAAGGACAGUAAGGUCUUCAUUCCAUGGAGUGACUAGUCAGUCAACAAAAGUAAAAAUGCCUCAUUUCAUCAAAUCAACUUUUCCAGUAAAGGCCAGAGUUCAAAUACUGUAAGCAUGAGAAUAGAAUGGAGCUGUCACUAAAGAGAGUACAAGGUCAAGAACCAGAAAUGUCUCCAAGCUUUCUGCAGUGUGAGCAAAGAUAGCCUCGACUGGACAAAUAACACUUCUGACCCCGUGGUACCCCCACAUGACUGGUAUGCUGCCCCUGGACUUUGUGUCUCUCUAAAAUCACUACCAUUCACUGAGAUCUGACCAGGUGAGGCACUCACCAACGCUACAGAAGCAACACACAGGUUUCCAAUCCUCUCAAACACAGAUACAACCCCCAUCCUCCAAUGUGCAUGGAAGAACUUUAAAUCUCAGAGAGAGUAAGCAAAAUCACACAAUUUAGUGGUUUAGACCUAUUCCAAAGUCUUCUUUUCACUGUAACACAAAACCCAACAGUAUCCCACCCAAUUUAUGAAGUCAAAUUUGUUUGCUUAAAAAAAAAAUCAGCUGGGCAUGGGCUCACACCUGUAAUCCCAGCACUUUGGGCCUAAACAGGCAGAUCGCUUGGUCUCAGGAGCUCGAGACCAGCCUGGGUAACAUGACAAAACCCUGUCUCUACAAAAAAAUACAAAAAAAAAAAAAUUUUUUUUUAAAUCAACUCUUUAACAGAGAAACCUUAAUCCCAAAGAUUUCCUUAACUGUUGUGGCCCUACUGCAGCAUAGGGCUCCCCACUUCAUUCACUGUCUCUCCUGCUUCAAGAUGUUUCUUCCCUGUGGAUGAAGAACCAGGAGAUCACACACAGAAAUGGGAAAAUAUCUGGGUAAAAACAUUCAAAGAAUAGCACAAAAUGGUUUGGGACUUCCAAAUAAGACUCUCAGGAAAGCAGGCUACAGCUCUACCUCAAAACCCGCCACCUCCUAUAACGAAGGACUGGUUUUCCAAUGGCCUAUAUACACAUUUUGCUGCACUCUACAAACAGAAAGCAAUAGGCUUGAAUUUCACCAUGAUAUGUGGUACACCUACCUUAUUAUUCACUUAUCUUUCAACCUUCCAUUACUUUUUGAUUAGUAACAAAAUUAAGACUCAUUUCUCAAAAAUAUCAGAAAACCAACCGUUUCAUUCUUACUCGAGUUCUUCCAGCAUGUUCAUUUUGAACUGUUUACCUCCCAUGAAAUAAAAAGUCUCUUGACUCUGA